GGGGCGCGGCCUCCUGUCUGCACCGGCAGCACCAUGUCGCUCACUGUCGUCAGCAUGGCGUGCGUUGGGUUCUUCUUGCUGCAGGGGGCCUGGCCACUCAUGGGUGGUCAGGACAAACCCUUCCUGUCUGCCCGGCCCAGCACUGUGGUGCCUCGAGGAGGACACGUGGCUCUUCAGUGUCACUAUCGUCGUGGGUUUAACAAUUUCAUGCUGUACAAAGAAGACAGAAGCCACGUUCCCAUCUUCCACGGCAGAAUAUUCCAGGAGAGCUUCAUCAUGGGCCCUGUGACCCCAGCACAUGCAGGGACCUACAGAUGUCGGGGUUCACGCCCACACUCCCUCACUGGGUGGUCGGCACCCAGCAACCCCCUGGUGAUCAUGGUCACAGGAAACCACAGAAAACCUUCCCUCCUGGCCCACCCAGGGCCCCUGCUGAAAUCAGGAGAGACAGUCAUCCUGCAAUGUUGGUCAGAUGUCAUGUUUGAGCACUUCUUUCUGCACAGAGAGGGGAUCUCUGAGGACCCCUCACGCCUCGUUGGACAGAUCCAUGAUGGGGUCUCCAAGGCCAACUUCUCCAUCGGUCCCUUGAUGCCUGUCCUUGCAGGAACCUACAGAUGUUAUGGUUCUGUUCCUCACUCCCCCUAUCAGUUGUCAGCUCCCAGUGACCCCCUGGACAUCGUGAUCACAGGUCUAUAUGAGAAACCUUCUCUCUCAGCCCAGCCGGGCCCCACGGUUCAGGCAGGAGAGAACGUGACCUUGUCCUGUAGCUCCUGGAGCUCCUAUGACAUCUACCAUCUGUCCAGGGAAGGGGAGGCCCAUGAACGUAGGCUCCGUGCAGUGCCCAAGGUCAACAGAACAUUCCAGGCAGACUUUCCUCUGGGCCCUGCCACCCACGGAGGGACCUACAGAUGCUUCGGCUCUUUCCGUGCCCUGCCCUGCGUGUGGUCAAACUCAAGUGACCCACUGCUUGUUUCUGUCACAGGAAACCCUUCAAGUAGUUGGCCUUCACCCACAGAACCAAGCUCCAAAUCUGGUAUCUGCAGACACCUGCAUGUUCUGAUUGGGACCUCAGUGGUCAUCUUCCUCUUCAUCCUCCUCCUCUUCUUUCUCCUUUAUCGCUGGUGCUCCAACAAAAAGAAUGCUGCUGUAAUGGACCAAGAGCCUGCGGGGGACAGAACAGUGAAUAGGCAGG